GCAGGCGCAGGCGCAGGCGAGGGGCUGGGUGGCGGUUGAGACAGCGGCGGUACUGGGAGGCGUAGGUGAGGGUCGCGAGGCUGCCCGAGCUUCUGAGCGAGCGCGGUGCUUUUGGGAACGCGGGACGGGCGAUCUGCGGCGCCAGGAGCUGGGCCGAGGCGCGGCGGCGCGGCUGCCGGCUGCCCUGUGAAUGGGAAGUUACGCGAAGUCCACCCAGCGUUUCUGAGGCAAUCUGAAGGCAAAUCCUGUUUAGACCCAGGCGAAGGUUCCCGGUGACCCGGGCUCUCACCAGCCAAUUGUCCCUUGCCGUCCUCCUGAGGGUGCCUGGAGCUUAAGCACUGUGUGCUCUUGGCCUCCACACUGGGGAUGCCGCUGACUCCCACUGUCCAGGGCUUCCAGUGGAUUCUCCGAGGCCCUGAUGUAGAAACUUCCCCAUUGGGUGCACCAAGAGCAGCCUCACAUGGUGUGGGCUGACAUCAAGAGCUGCCAGAUCCAACAGGAAGAUGGCCAAUCUUUCCUAAGCUGCUCACCUUACAAGAAAACGAAUCGUACUGCUAAGAAUUCAAACUUCAGCAGUCAUGGGGAGCCUUGGGAGGAGCCCGAAUCACUGAUGGAAUUGGACAGUGCAUGGAGAUGGUUCAGCAGGACAAGGUGCUGAAAACUCAUCCCCGUGUGACCUCAAGUAAGCCAUGUAACUCUGUGAACCUGCAGUUUUAUCAUUUUUAAAAUAAAGAAACAUGACAGAUUUUCAUUAUGACACAGAAUGUCAGGUCUCCCAGAUGCCAGAAAAUACAUUUACUUAAAGCCAUUGAUACGUCUUAAAGCGGUUUCCUUACAGUGUCAUUGGAGGACAGUGUGGAGUGCAGAGAGACAUGCUUUGAAAUGGGAUUGAUCCAGUGCUCCUUCCUUCACUACCACAUGAAUGCUGGGCAGCCCAGGGUCAACCCACCGCACCCUCAACUCAGACGGUUACCUGGCACGCUGGCCACAGUCUACCUCACUCUUAUCAGAGUCUGAGCUACUGGCAGUGCUUUCAGCUCUGAGUUCAGGCACCUCGAACCUUGUUUUUGUGGUGAAGGAUCCUAAAGUGCUGUGGGGAGUGAUCACAUUUUUCACAACAUCCCUGGCUCCACCUCUUCUGCCACAAACGUCAGCAUGGUGGUAUCAGCCGGCCCUUGGUCCAGCGAGAAGGCAGAGACGAACAUUCUAGAAAUGAAUGAGAAAUUGCGCCCCCAGCUGGCAGAGAAGAAACAGCAGUUCAGAAACCUCAAAGAGAAAUGUUUUGUAACUCAACUGGCCGGCUUCCUGGCCAACCGACAGAAGAAAUACAAGUAUGAAGAGUGUAAAGACCUCAUAAAAUUUAUGCUGAGGAAUGAGCGACAGUUCAAGGAGGAGAAGCUUGCAGAGCAGCUCAAGCAAGCUGAGGAGCUCAGGCAAUAUAAAGUCCUGGUUCACUCUCAGGAACGAGAGCUGACCCAGUUAAGGGAGAAGUUACGGGAAGGGAGAGAUGCCUCCCGCUCAUUGAAUCAGCAUCUCCAGGCCCUCCUCACUCCGGAUGAGCCAGACAAGUCCCAGGGGCAGGACCUGCAAGAACAGCUGGCUGAGGGGUGUAGACUGGCACAGCAACUUUUCCAAAAGCUCAGCCCAGAAAAUGACGAAGAUGAGGAUGAAGAUGUUCAAGUUGAGGAGGCUGAGAAAGUACUGGAAUCAUCUGCCCCCAGGGAGGUGCAGAAGGCUGAAGAAAGCAAAGUCCCUGAGGACUCACUGGAGGAAUGUGCCAUCACUUGUUCAAAUAGCCACGGCCCUUGUGACUCCAACCAGCCUCACAAGAACAUCAACAUCACAUUUGAGGAAGACAAAGUCAACUCAGCUCUGGUUGUAGACAGAGAAUCCUCUCAUGAUGAAUGUCAGGAUGCUGUAAACAUUCUCCCAGUCCCUGGCCCCACCUCUUCUGCCACAAACGUCAGCAUGGUGGUAUCAGCCGGCCCUUUGUCCAGCGAGAAGGCAGAGAUGAACAUUCUAGAAAUCAACGAGAAAUUGCAUCCCCAGCUGGCAGAGAAGAAACAGCAGUUCAGAAACCUCAAAGAGAAAUGUUUUGUAACUCAACUGGCUGGCUUCCUGGCCAACCAGCAGAACAAAUACAAAUAUGAAGAGUGCAAAGACCUCAUAAAAUCUAUGCUGAGGAAUGAGCGACAGUUCAAGGAGGAGAAGCUUGCAGAGCAGCUCAAGCAAGCUGAGGAGCUCAGGCAAUAUAAAGUCCUGGUUCACUCUCAGGAACGAGAGCUGACCCAGUUAAGGGAGAAGUUACGGGAAGGGAGAGAUGCCUCCCGCUCAUUGAGUCAGCAUCUCCAGGCCCUCCUCACUCCGGAUGAGCCAGACAAGUCCCAGGGGCAGGACCUGCAAGAACAGCUGGCUGAGGGGUGUAGACUGGCACAGCACCUUGUCCAAAAGCUCAGCCCAGAAAAUGACGAAGAUGAGGAUGAAGAUGUUCAAGUUGAGGAGGCUGAGAAAGUACUGGAAUCAUCUGCCCCCAGGGAGGUGCAGAAGGCUGAAGAAAGCAAAGUCCCUGAGGACUCACUGGAGGAAUGUGCCAUCACUUGUUCAAAUAGCCACGGCCCUUGUGACUCCAACCAGCCUCACAAGAACAUCAACAUCACAUUUGAGGAAGACAAAGUCAACUCAGCUCUGGUUGUAGACAGAGAAUCCUCUCAUGAUGAAUGUCAGGAUGCUGUAAACAUUCUCCCAGUCCCUGGCCCCACCUCUUCUGCCACAAACGUCAGCAUGGUGGUAUCAGCCGGCCCUUUGUCCAGCGAGAAGGCAGAGAUGAACAUUCUAGAAAUGAAUGAGAAAUUGCGCCCCCAGCUGGCAGAGAAGAAACAGCAGUUCAGAAACCUCAAAGAGAAAUGUUUUGUAACUCAACUGGCCGGCUUCCUGGCCAACCAGCAGAACAAAUACAAAUAUGAAGAGUGCAAAGACCUCAUAAAAUCUAUGCUGAGGAAUGAGCGACAGUUCAAGGAGGAGAAGCUUGCAGAGCAGCUCAAGCAAGCUGAGGAGCUCAGGCAAUAUAAAGUCCUGGUUCACUCUCAGGAACGAGAGCUGACCCAGUUAAGGGAGAAGUUACGGGAAGGGAGAGAUGCCUCCCGCUCAUUGAGUCAGCAUCUCCAGGCCCUCCUCACUCCGGAUGAGCCAGACAAGUCCCAGGGGCAGGACCUCCAAGAACAGCUGGCUGAGGGGUGUAGACUGGCACAGCACCUUGUCCAAAAGCUCAGCCCAGAAAAUGACAACGAUGACGAUGAAGAUGUUCAAGUUGAGGUGGCUGAGAAAGUGCAGAAAUCGUCUGCCCCCAGGGAGAUGCCGAAGGCUGAAGAAAAGGAAGUCCCUGAGGACUCACUGGAGGAAUGUGCCAUCACUUGUUCAAAUAGCCAUGGCCCUUAUGACUCCAACCAGCCACAUAGGAAAACCAAAAUCACAUUUGAGGAAGACAAAGUCGACUCAACUCUCAUUGGCUCAUCCUCUCAUGUUGAAUGGGAGGAUGCUGUACACAUUAUCCCAGAAAAUGAAAGUGAUGAUGAGGAAGAGGAAGAAAAAGGGCCAGUGUCUCCCAGGAAUCUGCAGGAGUCUGAAGAGGAGGAAGUCCCCCAGGAGUCCUGGGAUGAAGGUUAUUCGACUCUCUCAAUUCCUCCUGAAAUGUUGGCCUCGUACCAGUCUUACAGCGGCACAUUUCACUCAUUAGAGGAACAGCAAGUCUGCAUGGCUGUUGACAUAGGCGGACAUCGGUGGGAUCAAGUGAAAAAGGAGGACCAAGAGGCAACAGGUCCCAGGCUCAGCAGGGAGCUGCUGGAUGAGAAAGGGCCUGAAGUCUUGCAGGACUCACUGGAUAGAUGUUAUUCAACUCCUUCAGGUUAUCUUGAACUGACUGACUCAUGCCAGCCCUACAGAAGUGCCUUUUACAUAUUGGAGCAACAGCGUGUUGGCUGGGCUCUUGACAUGGAUGAAAUUGAAAAGUACCAAGAAGUGGAAGAAGACCAAGACCCAUCAUGCCCCAGGCUCAGCAGGGAGCUGCUGGAUGAGAAAGAGCCUGAAGUCUUGCAGGACUCACUGGAUAGAUGUUAUUCGACUCCUUCAGGUUAUCUUGAACUGCCUGACUUAGGCCAGCCCUACAGAAGUGCUGUUCACUCAUUGGAGGAACAGUACCUUGGCUUGGCUCUUGACGUGGACAGAAUUAAAAAGGACCAGGAAGAGGAAGAAGACCAAGGCCCACCAUGCCCCAGGCUCAGCAGGGAGCUGCUGGAGGCAGUAGAGCCUGAAGUCUUGCAGGACUCACUGGAUAGAUGUUAUUCAACUCCUUCCAGUUGUCUUGAACAGCCUGACUCCUGCCUGCCCUAUGGAAGUUCCUUUUAUGCAUUGGAGGAAAAACAUGUUGGCUUUUCUCUUGACGUGGGAGAAAUUGAAAAGAAGGGGAAGGGGAAGAAAAGAAGGGGAAGAAGAUCAACGAAGAAAAGAAGGAGAAGGGGAAGAAAAGAAGGGGAAGAAGAUCAAAACCCACCAUGCCCCAGGCUCAGCAGGGAGCUGCUGGAUGAGAAAGGGCCUGAAGUCUUGCAGGACUCACUGGAUAGAUGUUAUUCAACUCCUUCAGGUUAUCUUGAACUGACUGACUCAUGCCAGCCCUACAGAAGUGCCUUUUACAUAUUGGAGCAACAGCGUGUUGGCUGGGCUCUUGACAUGGAUGAAAUUGAAAAGUACCAAGAAGUGGAAGAAGACCAAGACCCAUCAUGCCCCAGGCUCAGCAGGGAGCUGCUGGAUGAGAAAGAGCCUGAAGUCUUGCAGGACUCACUGGAUAGAUGUUAUUCGACUCCUUCAGGUUAUCUUGAACUGCCUGACUUAGGCCAGCCCUACAGAAGUGCUGUUCACUCAUUGGAGGAACAGUACCUUGGCUUGGCUCUUGACGUGGACAGAAUUAAAAAGGACCAGGAAGAGGAAGAAGACCAAGGCCCACCAUGCCCCAGGCUCAGCAGGGAGCUGCUGGAGGCAGUAGAGCCUGAAGUCUUGCAGGACUCACUGGAUAGAUGUUAUUCAACUCCUUCCAGUUGUCUUGAACAGCCUGACUCCUGCCUGCCCUAUGGAAGUUCCUUUUAUGCAUUGGAGGAAAAACAUGUUGGCUUUUCUCUUGACGUGGGAGAAAUUGAAAAGAAGGGGAAGGGGAAGAAAAGAAGGGGAAGAAGAUCAACGAAGAAAAGAAGGAGAAGGGGAAGAAAAGAAGGGGAAGAAGAUCAAAACCCACCAUGCCCCAGGCUCAGCAGGGAGCUGCUGGAUGAGAAAGGGCCUGAAGUCUUGCAGGACUCACUGGAUAGAUGUUAUUCAACUCCUUCAGGUUAUCUUGAACUGACUGACUCAUGCCAGCCCUACAGAAGUGCCUUUUACAUAUUGGAGCAACAGCGUGUUGGCUGGGCUCUUGACAUGGAUGAAAUUGAAAAGUACCAAGAAGUGGAAGAAGACCAAGACCCAUCAUGCCCCAGGCUCAGCAGGGAGCUGCUGGAUGAGAAAGAGCCUGAAGUCUUGCAGGACUCACUGGAUAGAUGUUAUUCGACUCCUUCAGGUUAUCUUGAACUGCCUGACUUAGGCCAGCCCUACAGAAGUGCUGUUCACUCAUUGGAGGAACAGUACCUUGGCUUGGCUCUUGACGUGGACAGAAUUAAAAAGGACCAGGAAGAGGAAGAAGACCAAGGCCCACCAUGCCCCAGGCUCAGCAGGGAGCUGCUGGAGGCAGUAGAGCCUGAAGUCUUGCAGGACUCACUGGAUAGAUGUUAUUCAACUCCUUCCAGUUGUCUUGAACAGCCUGACUCCUGCCUGCCCUAUGGAAGUUCCUUUUAUGCAUUGGAGGAAAAACAUGUUGGCUUUUCUCUUGACGUGGGAGAAAUUGAAAAGAAGGGGAAGGGGAAGAAAAGAAGGGGAAGAAGAUCAACGAAGAAAAGAAGGAGAAGGGGAAGAAAAGAAGGGGAAGAAGAUCAAAACCCACCAUGCCCCAGGCUCAGCAGGGAGCUGCUGGAUGAGAAAGGGCCUGAAGUCUUGCAGGACUCACUGGAUAGAUGUUAUUCAACUCCUUCAGGUUAUCUUGAACUGACUGACUCAUGCCAGCCCUACAGAAGUGCCUUUUACAUAUUGGAGCAACAGCGUGUUGGCUGGGCUCUUGACAUGGAUGAAAUUGAAAAGUACCAAGAAGUGGAAGAAGACCAAGACCCAUCAUGCCCCAGGCUCAGCAGGGAGCUGCUGGAUGAGAAAGAGCCUGAAGUCUUGCAGGACUCACUGGAUAGAUGUUAUUCGACUCCUUCAGGUUAUCUUGAACUGCCUGACUUAGGCCAGCCCUACAGAAGUGCUGUUCACUCAUUGGAGGAACAGUACCUUGGCUUGGCUCUUGACGUGGACAGAAUUAAAAAGGACCAGGAAGAGGAAGAAGACCAAGGCCCACCAUGCUCCAGGCUCAGCAGGGAGCUGCUGGAGGCAGUAGAGCCUGAAGUCUUGCUGGACUCACUGGAUAGAUGUUAUUCAACUCCUUCCAGUUGUCUUGAACAGCCUGACUCCUGCCUGCCCUAUGGAAGUUCCUUUUAUGCAUUGGAGGAAAAACAUGUUGGCUUUUCUCUUGACGUGGGAGAAAUUGAAAAGAAGGGGAAGGGGAAGAAAAGAAGGGGAAGAAGAUCAACGAAGAAAAGAAGGAGAAGGGGAAGUAAAGAAGGGGAAGAAGAUCAAAACCCACCAUGCCCCAGGCUCAGCGGUGUGCUGAUGGAAGUGGAAGAGCCUGAAGUCUUACAGGACUCACUGGAUAGAUGUUAUUCGACUCCGUCAAUGUACUUUGAACUACCUGACUCAUUCCAGCACUACAGAAGUGUGUUUUACUCAUUUGAGGAACAGCACAUCAGCUUCGCCCUUGACGUGGACAAUAGGUUUCUUACUUUGAUGGGAACAAGUCUCCACCUGGUCUUCCAGAUGGGAGUCAUAUUCCCACAGUAAGCAGCCCUUUCUAAGCCGAGAGAUGUCAUUCCUGCAGGCAGGACCUAUAGGCACGUGAAGAUUUGAAUGAAACUAUAGUUCCAUUUGGAAGCCCAGACAUAGGAUGGGUCAGUGGGCGUGGCUCUAUUCCUAUUCUCAGACCAUGCCAGUGGCAACCUGUGCUCAGUCUGAAGACAAUGGACCCAAGUUAGGUGUGACACGUUCACAUAACUGUGCAGCACAUGCCGGGAGUGAUCAGUCAGACAUUUUAAUUUGAACCACGUAUCUCUGGGUAGCUACAAAGUUCCUCAGGGAUUUCAUUUUGCAGGCAUGUCUCUGAGCUUCUAUACCUGCUCAAGGUCAGUGUCAUCUUUGUGUUUAGCUCAUCCAAAGGUGUUACCCUGGUUUCAAUGAACCUAACCUCAUUCUUUGUAUCUUCAGUGUUGAAUUGUUUUAGCUGAUCCAUCUUUAACACAGGAGGGAUCCUUGGCUGAGGAUUGUAUUUCAGAACCACCAACUGCUCUUGACAAUUGUUAACCCGCUAGGCUCCUUUGGUUAGAGAAGCCACAGUCCUUCAGCCUCCAAUUGGUGUUAGUACUUAAGAAGACCACAGCUAGAUGGACAAACAGCAUUGGGAGGCCUUAGCCCUGCUCCUCUCGAUUCCAUCCUGUAGAGAACAGGAGUCAGGAGCCGCUGGCAGGAGACAGCAUGUCACCCAGGACUCUGCCGGUGCAGAAUAUGAACAACGCCAUGUUCUUGCAGAAAACGCUUAGCCUGAGUUUCAUAGGAGGUAAUCACCAGACAACUGCAGAAUGUAGAACACUGAGCAGGACAACUGACCUGUCUCCUUCACAUAGUCCAUAUCACCACAAAUCACACAACAAAAAGGAGAAGAGAUAUUUUGGGUUCAAAAAAAGUAAAAAGAUAAUAUAGCUGCAUUUCUUUAGUUAUUUUGAACCCCAAAUAUUUCCUCAUCUUUUUGUUGUUGUCAUUGAUGGUGGUGACAUGGACUUGUUUAUAGAGGACAGGUCAGCUGUCUGGCUCAAUGAUCUACAUUCUGAAGUUGUCUGAAAAUGUCUUCAUGAUUAAAUUCAGCCUAAACGUUUUGCCGGGAACACUGCAGAGACAAUGCUGUGAGUUUCCAACCUUAGCCCAUCUGCGGGCAGAGAAGGUCUAGUUUGUCCAUCAGCAUUAUCAUGAUAUCAGGACUGGUUACUUGGUUAAGGAGGGGUCUAGGAGAUGUGUCCCUUUUAGAGACACCUUACUUAUAAUGAAGUAUUUGGGAGGGUGGUUUUCAAAAGUAGAAAUGUCCUGUAUUCCGAUGAUCAUCCUGUAAACAUUUUAUCAUUUAUUAAUCAUCCCUGCCUGUGUCUAUUAUUAUAUUCAUAUCUCUACGCUGGAAACUUUCUGCCUCUAUGUUUACUGUGCCUUUGUUUUUGCUAGUGUGUGUUGUUGAAAAAAAAAACAUUCUCUGCCUGAGUUUUAAUUUUUGUCCAAAGUUAUUUUAAUCUAUACAAUUAAAAGCUUUUGCCUAUCA